CUCUUCUGCUCACUCGUCCCCACCUUGUUCUAUAGGACGUUUGGUGGUUCCUCCUGCCAGGAUGCCUUAACGUUGAUAUUCACGGAAGGCUGAGGGUCGGGGGAGUAAUAGGCAACUCCUUCUUUAACCACCAGCCUCAUUAUUCAUUAUUUUCUUUAUGUAGUGGAUUUUUGCCAGACAUGCAUUACAAUCUCAGAUGAUUCUACUCUAUACCCAUUUGUGGGGAAUCACUGUUCUCUAAGAGGAAUUAAAGGAGAUUUCACAUUCUCUCUCUGGCUUGCCCCGCCACCCCCGACCACCUCCCCCCGCACCGCCCCCACCUAUAGACACACUCUGGGUUGCCCUGGGAGGGCAGUGGGCAGUGGGAUAUUGGAUAUUGUGUUUCAGAAGGUGUACAGGCUCCCACAGACCCUGGCUCAGGCAGGGAAGGGGGACAGGAUUUACCCAGGGUGGCUGACUUCGCACACAUGGCGAGGGAGAACCUCCUGCCUCAUCCACAGAACUGUGGCCUGGCAACAUGAGACCUGGCAGAGGGAGGAGGGGUGGCUGGAAUGUGAGGAGACCUAAGGGGUAUGCAGAGCAGUUGGGGUGGGUCGAAUUAUUCCCAGCAAGCAACAUGACCAGGGUUCCAUAUUGAAAGACCACCCCGACAGGUUCAGAGCAAGGUGAGGCUGGGGCAGAGGAGACCUAAGAGAUUUCUGCAACAGCCAGGUAAGAAAUGAAGAGAAUCAUAGCUGAGAGGCUUGCUUGCGGGCUGCAGAAGAGUGGGUACAUCGGAGAGACUCGGGAGCUGCAUCUGGAAGAGUCUGGUCCCUGACCCAUCUGGGGGUGCAGGGGCUGGCAGGUGUUCUUAGUCAGUGCAUCUUUCAUGGUACUUAAGAACAGUUCUUGAACAAUUCUCCUAACCUUGUUUGUACUGUUAGUUUGCCCUGAAUUGUAACCCCAGAAAAGACUUUUGUGACUUUUCUGGUCCAAACCAGGCAGGAGACAAACUGGGACCAAAUUAGUCAGGAGACUUGCUCGAGGACACAGCCUGUGAGAAGCAGGCCAGGCUCCAGCCCGUGUCUUCUUCGCGUUGUGUUUACCCGUCAUGUGAAAUGCAGUAGGACUGCAAACCUGAAUAAUUUUGUCGAUAGAUGGCAUUUUUGCGUAAAGGCGUCUCUUAUUUUUUACGUGGAUACUCUUUAAAAUGAAAAUCAAAAAAGUUAUUCUGGAAGUAAACUGGCUCAUGAAAUGACAACAUAUGGUGACAGCAUUUCGUCUUAUUCAACCUAGAAUGUCAUCUUAGUUCCCGGAUGAUAAGGGAUAUUUGGAAUGAGGUAUUUAUUUUAUGUUGUAGAAUAUUGGAUAACUGCCACAGUACCGGGCAUAUAGUGAGUAUUCACAAAACAUUGGUUGCGUGAAACGAAUUGUGUGAGUCACUUUUUCUUGUAUCUUAUUCAGAACGAUGCUUCAGAGGGCUUUUGUGACUCACUUGUCUCCAGUUGCUGAUGCAGCUGUAAUGCUGUUAGACACAGGGAUCAAAUGAACAUACGCUGCUGUUCGUGGUUUUGGGGGUUCUAUUUUGGGGAGUGCUAUGUCUGUUUUUAGUUUCUUGAAACUGCCUUUUAUGCACAAAACCGAAGUAGACUGAAUCUAUAACUGCAGAGCCACACAGAAUCUGGUGCGUCGUGUUUCCUGUCCAGCAUUGCCACUUCCAGGUUUUUCAUCUAACUUGAAUAAAACAUGUUUAUUUUUUACAGAAUUUCCACAAAAUUUUAUUUUUGAAGUUGCUUUUCAGAAAAUCUGUUUUUAACUGGUAAAAUACAUGUCACAUCUAAAUACACAGUUCAGUCAUUUAAGUAUGUAAGUUGCGCAACCAGUCUCCAGAACUGUUUCAUCUGAAAUGAUGUGUUUUUUGUUUGUUCGUUUGUUUGUUUUUGAGACGGAGUCUCACCCUGCCGCCCAGGCUGGAGUGCAGUAGCACAAUCUCGGCUCACUGCAACUUCCGCCUCCUGGGUUCAAGCGAUUCUCCUGCCUCAGUCUCCUGAGUAGCUGGAACUACAGGCGCGUGCUACCACGCCCGGCUAAUUUUUUGUAUUUUUAGUAGAGACGGAGUUUCACCAUGUUAGCCAGGAUGGUCUCCAUCUCCUGACCUCAUGAUCCACCCACCUCGGCCUCCCAAAGUGCAGGGAUUACAGGCAUGAGCCACUGCGCCCGGCCGCAGUGAUGUUUUUUGAAGGAGUUCUGUUAGAAUUGAAAAGGUAGGAAGCUGGAGGCGCAGUGUCCACAAAUGUAACAGAGUGUCUUGGUGUCAGGAAAACACAGCAGGGCACAGGUCAGGCAUGUGGUUUGGGCAGCAGCAGUGGGAGCAGGGAGCAGCUCAGUGGUAGAUGGGAAGGCAAACUGCUUAGGAGGAUGCCACACUUAGGAAUGAGUUUCUUUAGGCGAAGUCUGCACGUGCCUGGUUUACCUCCAGUAAGUGGGGCUCCAGCAUAAAGGUGAAGGCUCUGGAUCACAGCCAGCAGACUCUUUGUGCUGUGUAAAGGGUUGGCGGGUAAAUGUUUUAGGGUUUUUGCAGGCCGUGGGAUCUCGCUCCCAGCUGCUCAGCUUAGCCACUGUAAUGCAAAAACAGCUGUAGACAGUAACAAAAGUGAGUGUAACUGUGUCCCAGUAGAAGUUUUAAUGGGGGAUUUUGGCCAGUGGGCCGUAGUGUGCCGACCCCUGCCCUGAGUUACAGAUGUAAGUGUUUCUGUUUUGGGCCUGGUACUACGACUGCUGUUUCCUCUCAAGUUAUCCAGUUUUUGAAAGUACGCUUUCUCCGCAGUGAGAUGGGAGCAGUACCUGUAAAACCUGUGCCUGGCAUGCGAUGACAUGAGAUAAUCUGUAAAAUGCCACUCGGAAAGUAGAAGUUACUGAUGUGUUUUUUGUGAGCGGUGACUCUGAAAACUGGCUUUUAAAUCAUAGUUCGUUCAUGGGUUCCCGUGUUUAAUGUAGUAGCCAACUUAAGACUUACGAGAGGGCCAAACCACCGUCACAGACACCCGAGAGGACGCAGCAGAGACAGAUGUUAAUUUCUCUGUCCAGUAACGGGAUGGCUUUUCCAGGAUUUCGGGGGACUGUGUUCCUUGUCAUUGAGGGGUCCAGGGUCUUCCAUUUUGCUUUACUGCCGUCUCCUGUGGCAUUGUCCUUCACCGGUCAGUAGCGUGGCUGCUGUGCUUAGGUGACAGACAGCUGCAGGAGAGGAAAGAGCCUGGAGACACAGAGCUCAGAGCCAGGUCUUAAGCACAAGCCAAAAGGGGAGCGGGUCUCUCACUCACACUCUGCUUGGGGGGGUCUUGGUUCACACCUAACUGGACAGAAGGCCCGAUAGCCGGAGUCAGACCACAGUCUGUCACCACAGGGGAAGGGGGACAGAUACAUUGGCGAUGAGGUCGCAGUCUGUGCGACGUGACGGAAACAAAUCCUUACAUCCCAAAGUGAGUCCCCAGCAGGCUUUCCUCUCUUUGGUGGACUGGGUUUUUGUUUCUCAGGUUUCAGAUAUAAGGCGUCCAAAUACCACUCGCGGAAUUCUUAGCGUAUACCAAGGUCAGAUGUUUAAGAAAUGCUAUUGCACAAUGUAGUUUAAUUGACUUUUAGGUUUAAAAGCUCCUAAUUUGAGAUUCAAAUAGGCUUCUAACAAGUAUUUCCAUUCGUAAGAAUCCUGGCUUCUUAGGAAUCGGUCACCUGUAUUUGUAGUUUUGGUUUUGCUGUAUAGUAAUUUAACAUUAUAUACAUUUAUAGCUUUACAUUAUAUAAGGAAUUUAUCAUUUAACAUUAUAAAUUGUUUAUAAUUUAACAUUAUAUAAAUGCCGUAAUUUGGGGUGUCCUUAGAUAUUUGCCCUGAAUUUGUCUCUCCUAGAAAAUCAUUCUGGCUGUAAUCGUAGAUACAAGGACUUGGGAAUCUUCUCAGAGUAUAAACCAGCAGAUCAGUCCAGAUGGAAACGUUUCCCUUAGGGUUCCUUCCUUUAAAUUUGUGUUAUAUGGCUUUUAGUUCUUCCUCUGCCAUAACAGGUGAGCUUGGGAAUACAUUUGUGAUUAAACUUACAUUUGGGCAGGUAUGGAAGUGUCUUGUGAUUAGUUACCAAAGCUUAACGUGACCUUUAAAUAAGGAACAUAAUUAAUGGGCUUCCAGUCAAAUAUAUCAAUAAUUUGAGGGAAGAAUCUUAAAUUGCCAGGCAUUGCCUCUCCCCACUCCUUCCACCCGUUGGGGCUGGCCUUGAACUCCUGGGCUCAAGUGAUCCUCCUGCCUCAGCCUCCUGAGUAGCUUGGACUACAGGCAUGUACCACCGCACCUGGCCGGAAAAUCUCAAAUUGCAUAAUGCCACUUUCUUUGGGAAGAAAUCAAGCAAAAUUUGUGAUUCUUGAGUAUCUGUAUAGAUGUAUACUUGUGAAGUAGGUAAACAAAGAAUAAAAGAAUUAAGACUAAACAUGCUUUGCCCCUUUUUGUUCUAGGAAUGUACCAGUAGUUCACUGAAUUGCUGGGGUCACAUACAGCCAAUGUGGUAUAUUGAAGGGUUUUUUUAAAAUUAUUUUUUCUUUCAAAUACAAAUGAGGUCUUGCUAUAUUUCUUAGGCUGUCCUCGAGCUCCUGAGCUCUAGCGGUUCCCUUGCCUUGACCUCCCAAAGUGCUGGGAUUAUAGGCAUGAGCCACCAUGCCCAGCCUAUAUCGAAUGUUUGACAAAUACAUUUGAAGCCAGGGCAUUUACAUUUAAAUUGUGGCUUUAUUGCUGGUGUUGGCUAAUCGUCCUAUAGUUCGCAUAGUGUAUAUGGUUCCUAGUGUAUAUAGUUUAUAGUCUAGUCAUGGAUCUCGGGGUGUAAUCCCGCUUGGUGGCAUUACAGUGCUGUGGCUUCUCUCAAGUUAGUUUGACAUGAGUUAUACCCUAAGAUAAUAACAGUGGUUAUCACUAGGUAGACAGAAUAGGUUUAAUGUUUCUUUUUACCUCUCUGAGUUUUCCUGGUUUCUGCCAGUAAACAUGGGUUAUGCCGUAAACCUUCCCACUUCUGACACCUGGCCUUCACAUCAGCAUGGGACACCAGAAAGUGCCUGAAUAAGAGCCAGCAAAGAAAAAUGUUUUCAUUUCUUCUAGUGUAAUUUAUACUUAUGGAUCUCAUGAGAAUUACAUUGUUUAGUUAGGGUAUGCUUAUUUUACAUAUAUGUUUUUUUUUUUUUUUUUGAGACUGCUUCUCGCUCUGUCACCCACGCUGGAGUACAGUGCUGUGAUCUUGGCUCACUCUGUCUCCCAGGUUCAAGUCAUUCUUCCGCCUCAGCUGGAAUUACAGGCGCCCUCCACUACACCUGGCUAAUUUUUGUAUUUUUAGUAGAGACAGGGUUUCACCACGUUAGCCAAGCUGAUCUCGAACUCCUGACCUCAAGUGAUUCACCUGCCUCAGCCUCCCAAAGUGUUGGGAUUACAGGCAUGAGCCACUGCUCCUGGUCUUGUAUGUCCAUUUUUAAUAUUUAUAUAUAAUUUAUAUUAACUAACUGGGGUGUCGACACUAUGUAUCUGGAAUUUGAAUCUAUUUGAUAGUCUCUCCUGCAAUUACCUCCUCCCUGGAGACAGGGUUUUUUUUUUUUUUUUUUGAGACGGAGUCUUGCUGUCACCCAAGCUGGAGUGCAGUGGCACUAUCUCGGCUCACUGCAAGCUCCGCCUCCCAGGUUCACACCAUUCUCUCGCCUCAGCCUCCUGAGUAGCUAGGACUACAGGCACCCGCCACCACGCCCGGUUAAUUUUGUUUUUGUAUUUUUAGUAGAAACAGGGUUUCACCGUGUUAGCUAGUAUGGUUUCGAUCUCCUGACCUCAUGAUCUGCCCGUCUCAGCCUCCCAAGGUGCUGGGAUUAGAGGCAUGGGCCACCACACCCGGCCAGCUUUUAAAUAAAAAAUGUAAUAAAAAGUUUGUAGCUUUCGGUUGACACAUGACUUAUACCUUUACCAUUAGCCUUUAAACUUUCUCACAUCUGUGAAAUUUUUGUUGUUCUUAUAGCUUAUAAUUUUCAUGUCUCUUUUUCUUUGGUUGAAAUCCUGACACAAAUAGUAGGAUAGCUUGGUUUUAUUUAGCAGUUAAUGUUGUUAACUAUUUCAGGAAAAUAAGAUGAUCCAAAAUAUGAUUAUUGCUCAGGUGUGAUAUAUGAGUAUGUAAGUACUGUAUAGUUUGCAAAGUAUAAUUAGUUUUGUAAUCUUAUAUGUGAAUAUGUUGCAUUAGAAGGAAUAUUUUUCAAAUGUCAGAGUAGGAUUAUGAGUGAUUCCUCCCGUUUCCAGAAUUUUAUAAUAAGUAUAUAUUGUUUUAUAAUAAUAAAGAAGGUUUAAAAAUAGUUCAUCGUAAGUGAUGUAAAUGUUUCUACUUGACGGCAUUUUAAGAGUCGCGUGGGUUAUGGGCGAGCUUAUGAAAUGCGGUUUGUAAGACUACUUUUCAUUCAUGAAUCCCUCUAUUUCAUUGUAGUCAGUCUGUUAUAAGACAUAUGUUGUGGAAUCUGUUCAAAACCUGGGGAGGAAGUGCAUGAGAUCUUAUCUUCUUGGCAUCAGAAGUGUACUCUUGAAAGUAGAAUUUUGACUUUUUGAGAUGCCACUGUUUAUCCUCCCACCCUUCACAGCUCUCCCUGUCUCCCUUCUCCCAACCCAACCCAUGCAUACAAAAAGUCAGGGUUUGUGAUUUAAUUUAGAAAUAGAGGCAAGAUUAGAAAAUGGAAUUGUGUGGAGACUUGGAGAUCAUGUAGCAUGCAGCAGAUCUGUUCUAGGAGGAGUAGGAAGCUCUGGUUGUGAGUGAUUGAAGACCACUGCACUGUUCAGAAGCAGCUGUCGCAUCCUCUUCCGUUCAGCACCUGAUUAUUAUGUAGCUUUAUUUAAUGGUGCAAAAUACCAAGUAGAGAACAAGGAACAUAAGGGCAAAAUUAAUGGCUGGAUAGCUGUUGUGGCUACGUAAUUCUGAUCUAAAAUUAGUUUAGAAAUUACAAUUGAAAAUGCAAUUGUGAAAUAUCAUUUUGAAAUACUUUAAAAUGCUGCCUAGCCUACUGAAAUGUUUCUCAGUUGAGGUACCCAUGUAAAAUGUGUGCGUACACAUGGACACACAAACAGGCUAAGAAAGAAGCAGAGGAGUAGAGACAUUUAAUUAGUUGAGACAGGUUUACCUCCAAUGAAAUUUUUCUUUUCUUUCAGUUUGUAGCACGUGGGUGGUCUAUGUGUUAAUGUUAAUAAUAAAACAGAAGUUACCCAUUCUUAGAUUACUUAACUCUACUGUCACUAGUGAUGGCUUUCCUGCCGAAGGCGCUCCGUAGCUACAUGAAGAGGGCACAGAGAAAAUUACUUGAAGCUUUCGAGUCACUUUCACUUUUAAAAGAUGCUGGUGGCCUUUGGAUCCCACUUUGCCCUGGUGCUUGGCCAAGGCCAGGGCAUCUGACCGCCCCUGAGCACAUGGAGGAAGAAGGUGGUAGAGGGAGGUGUGGAAAUCCACGCUGAUGGCCCUACCCUUGCUGGUGCCCUCUGUUGCUGGGACUCAGUGCCCCACCUGCUCACCAAGCAGAAGUGAUGUCAGAGUGGUCUCCAUGGCCAAGAGAGCAGGUUUUGUCAGGCAAGGAAGGAGCGUGAAGAUGCACACUCUCCUGGUGUGGAGCAUGGUGCUAUCCCCAGCGUGUCUUCCUCGGUGCCAGGAGUGUUGGUAUUGUGUGCACAUUAAAUAGAGGACUUUCCCACUCUUCUCUUUACUCUUAUGCAUUAUCUGACCCAAAUUUGGGUCCAUGGAGUAAACAUACUUGGUCAGAAACUGUGAAUAGUCAUUUCCAGCAUUUAAACCUUUCUUGCUGAUGACGCCAUUAAAAUACGCACAUGUGCAUGCACACAGCGUGACUGCGGCUGGAGAGGAAGGAGCGUUCGCCUGCUCCCGGGCAGCUGGUCAGGCUGGUGGCCCAGCCGUUUAUGCUUGCUCCGUGCUCCAGGGUGUGGCCCCUUGCCCAGGGGAAGAAAUGAAUGUUCUGAAAGAGCACAGCGUAUUCUUCAGUCUGCUCCAAGGUUGAUUCCCUCUGGAAAGCUUCCCUGGCCCCCUCACUGCUGUCUGGUCUCCCUCAGGUUUUCCCUGCUGGAGAGGCCUUCCCUGACCCAAGGAUAUGAUGCUGCAGCCCUGCCCUCGCUGCUGUCUCCCCAGCUUCGUGGUUCUCCAAAGCUCUCAUCCCCGUCUGACACACUCCUUGUUUGUUGCCUGCUUGCCGGACAGGCAUUUCUAGUUGUCUUGUCAAGAACCAGCCCGAGAGAGAGCUGAGAGCCAACCUCGGCUUUGCUGUGUGCAGUGGCUGCGGGGUGUGAGCAAGUUGCUGAACGCACAAACUAGAGUAUCCCUGAAAGUAAAACGUGCACAGUAACAGAGCUACCUCGUCGGAUUACACCAGUGCAUACAGGGUAGGUCCUUGGUAUAGCUUCCGAGAGAUGUUAGUUGUUAAUGUUAUUAUAUAAAAUCACAUAAAUUAUUUCACUUCAAUGGGAGAGGAGUGGUAAUAAGCAUUUUUUAAAAUUGGGUGCCUCUGAAGGGUGAAAGGGCUGGCUGACAGUUUAAACAUGUUGCCUAGAGUUUAGCUAAAAGGAUAGUUGAAUGAUUGUGCAGGGAGGUAGGUUAUUUUGGAAAUACAUGUAGGAUGAUUACUUUCAGCUAUGACAUCUUAACCUUUGGAUAAAUGUUUAUUAAGGGAAUACAUCAAUGCCAGGCUCUGCUGUGUGCUGUGAGACCUGCCUUCAAGGCACCUCUGUGGAGCCACGAGGGAGGCGUUUAGAACUCUGAAUUCUGAGAAUUCUAGUUGAUCCUCUUUGAAGGAUGCUUUUCCUCUCGUAUUUCUGAAGAUAUUGAUCUUCUGUAUUUGAAAGUCCCCUUGUCUUAGCUCUUGUUGCCAUAUUGUUUGGGAGUGGGGGGAGUUGGGGUUAAGGUUGGCUGUCUUGCCUUGGCUGGUCUGCCCCAGACCCCUGCCUGGCUGUCUGGGAAUCUGAGGGGUAGGAGGUGGGGGUAGGGAUGGGGAUGUCUUUUCUGAGCAGGCAAAGGCCCUGUGCAGAGUGUGUGUUCUCUUAGCUCUUGUUUAUUGGGCAUGACACGUCUCUUCUGUUGUAAUGUUUACGUAUUGACAGGAGCCACUUACAUUGUUGUCUGUGAUUAAUCUUUUUGUCCUUACCUGUAAACGAGAUACAGUAUCUACUCAUUCAUUUAUUCAGCAAGUACUUAGAGGGCAAUUACUCAGUGCUUGGCACCUAGAACAAAAUGAGUUUUGCUCUCAAGGAGUUUAAAAUUGUGAGGAUUAAAUGAGUGUGUUGAGAGAGAGAGAAGUAUGGUAUCUCAUAGCAGAUGCUUAAAAAUAUUUCUCUCUUCUUUUUGUAUAGGGCUUUUUAGUUUAGAAUACUGUGUUAAAGAACAAACAAUCCUACUCAUUGUUAAUUAUUAAUUACUUGCAUUUUAUUUCCACCUACCUCUUUCCACAAAGGAUCUGAAGUUUAGUGUAUUUUAUAUAUUUCUGUAAAUUUUUUUUUUUUGCUUAGAGCAGUGAGUAGAUAGAUGGAUGAAGGAAGGAAAAUGAAUGAAUUUAUUAUAAAUGAGAAGCCAGAGAAAAAGUACUACCAGUUUCCCCUACAAUCUACUUAACAUAGAUAAUUUGAGGAUGUUUUUUCCCUAAUAGGUUGCUUUAAAAAAAAAUUAAGUUUUUUGGAGGAGCUUUAGGUUCACAGCGAAAUUGAGUGGAAUGUGCAGAGAUUUCCCAAGUGGCGCCUGCCCCUACACGUGCACAGUCUCCCCCAAUAUGGACACCUUGUACCAGAGUGGUGGUACCUUUGUUACAAUUGGUGAACCUACAGUGACAUAUCAUUAUCACCCGAAGUCCACAGUUUACAAUAGGAGUCACUCUUGGUGUUGAACAUUCUGUGGGUUUAAACAAGUUUAUGACAGAUACCCUCAUAUAUGUAUCAUACAGAACAGUUCACUGUCCUAAAAAUCCUCUGUGAUCUGCCUGGUCAUCCUUCCUUCCCCUGUAACCCCUGGCAACCACUCAUCUUUUUACUGUCUUCAUAGUUUUGCCUUGUUUUGUUUUACAGUGUUAUAUAGUUGGAAUCGUACAGUAUGUAGCCUUUUCAGUUUGGCUUCUUUUACUUAGUAACAUGCAUUUAACUUUCUUCCGUGUCUUUUCAUGAUUUGAUAGUUCAUUUUUUAAAAAUGCUGAAUAGUAUUCCAUUAUCUGAAUGUGCCACAGUUUAUUCAUUCACCAACUGAAGGAUAUCUUGGUUGCUUCUGAGUUUUGGCAAUUAUGAACAAAAGUGCUGGAAACGCCCAUAUGCAGAUUUUUGUGUGGACACUAACUUUUCAGCUCUUUUGGGUAAAUACCAAGGAGCUCACUUGUUGGAUCCUAUAAGAGUAUGUUUAGUUUUGUAGGAAACUGCCAAACUGUCUUCCUAAGUGCCUGUAGCAUUUUGCAUUCUCCCCGGCAGUGAGCGAGAGUCCCUCUUGUUCCAUGUCCUCACCAGCAUUUCGCGUCGCUCCUCUCGGCCCUUCUACUAGGUGUGUCGUGGCAUCUCGUUGUUUGAAUUUGCAUCUCCCUGAUGACAUAUGAUGACUUUCACAUGCUUUUUUCUACCAUCUGUGUAACUUCGGCAAGGUGCUUGUUAAAGCCUUUGGCUACUUUUUAAUUGGGUUGUUUUCCUAUUUUUGAGUUUAGAAAUUCUUUGUAUAUUUUAGAUAAGUCUUAUAAGUCUGUGAAUAUUUUCUUUCAGUCUGUGACUUGUCUUAUUCUCUUGGCAGUGUCUUUUGCAGAGCAGAAGUUUUUAACUUUAAUUAAGUCCAGUUUAUCAAUUCUUACAUGGAGUGUGUCUUUGGUGUUGUGUCUAGAAAGUCAUCACCAAACCCAAGGUUGUCUAGAUUUUCUCCUCUGUUUUCUUUAGGAGUUUUGCAGUUUUGCCUUUUGCAUUUAGGCCUGUGAUCCUGUGAAGGGUAAGGUCUGUGUCUCGUUUCAUCUUCCUGCAUUUGGAUGUCCAGUUGUUCCAGCCCCAAGGGUUGAAAAGCCUGUCACUUCUCCGUGGGAUUGCUUUUGUUGGUUGCCUAUGCUCUGAAAACUGUUCAUAUUGCUUCCCUGGGAAUUUGACACUAUGGAAUUUAAAGCUUUACUAGCUUCCCUUCCCCACCCACCCUUCCCCAGAAAAACAAACCCACUCCCUCUUCUUCCCUCAGUCCCCUCUCCAGUGUUUUUCUUACCCUCUUUUUUGAAAGAAAACUUUCAGAAUGGUGCCUUUGUGAGGUAGCUGUGAAGUGAGAGUCCCCCCUCAGACUUCAUAUGAACUGGAGAUGGCAGACGUGGAGUCUUCAGCCUCACAGGGGUCGUGCUCAAAACCUAGGGUCCAAACCUGUGGCAUUUAACCCCACCGCACUCAACACUGUGUAAUGACAGAAACACUGACAGUUCUGAGUGUAACGCAUGACCCAAAGCUGGGUUGGGACCCCAGGGCUUCUAGAGCAGUUGCUCUUCCUCCGAGGACUCAAGUGGUGGAGCUGGGCUGCGGGAACCCUUGCUCCCCGCCCACAGCGCCACUGUGCUGUCCCCACUCACCAGGCCUCCACUGUCCCAGCGCCGCUGGAGUCUUUAGGCGGUGGUGGGGGUGGUUGGGUUUUUUAAGUAAGACAUUUCUUCAUUAAAUGCUAUACGUUAACACGGCGUUGAAUGUCUUUAUGUCGAAUAAGAUUCUACAAAAAGUCAGGUGUAGAUGAAAAAUAUCCUAGAAGGAGGUGAAUCUGUAGGUCAUAUUUGACCCACAGAUAUACUUUGGCUUGUAUUUCUUUUUUCUCUCUUUUCCUUUUCUCUGUCCCUUUCCCUUUCUCUCUCACUUGAACUGGUUGCCAGCACUUCAGUUAGACUUGACACAGAACAGCUGGAUUUCUAGCUUCCCUUUAAACCCGGCUGCACUGGGCCUGUGUGGCACGUCCUGGUCCCCCCGAGCUCCAUCCCUUCUGGCUUACAUCCACCUUGUCCCUAUGCAGCAGCUUUUUUAUGAGAAUUACGAGCAGAACAAAAAGGGGUACAUUAGAGAUCUCCAUAACAGUAAAAUUCACCAAGCUAUCACAUUACACCCCAACAAAAACCCACCCUACCAGUACAGGCUCCACAGCUACAUGCUGAGCCGCAAGAUAUCCGAGCUCCGCCAUCGCACAAUACAGCUGCACCGCGAAAUUGUCCUGAUGAGCAAAUACAGCAACACAGAAAUUCAUAAAGAGGACCUCCAGCUGGGAAUCCCUCCCUCCUUCAUGAGGUUUCAGCCCCGCCAGCGAGAGGAGAUUCUGGAAUGGGAGUUUCUGACUGGAAAAUACUUGUAUUCGGCAGUUGACGGCCAGCCCCCUCGAAGAGGAAUGGACUCCGCCCAGAGGGAAGCCUUGGACGACAUUGUCAUGCAGGUCAUGGAGAUGAUCAAUGCCAACGCCAAGACCAGAGGGCGCAUCAUUGACUUCAAAGAGAUCCAGUACGGCUACCGCCGGGUGAACCCCAUGUAUGGGGCUGAGUACAUCCUGGACCUGCUGCUUCUGUACAAAAAGCACAAAGGGAAGAAAAUGACGGUCCCUGUGAGGAGGCACGCGUAUUUACAGCAGACUUUCAGCAAAAUCCAGUUUGUGGAGCAUGAGGAGCUGGAUGCACAAGAGUUGGCCAAGAGAAUCAAUCAGGAAUCUGGAUCCUUGUCCUUUCUCUCAAACUCCCUGAAGAAGCUCGUCCCCUUUCAGCUCCCUGGGUCGAAGAGUGAGCACAAAGAACCCAAAGAUAAAAAGAUAAACAUACUGAUUCCUUUGUCUGGGCGUUUCGACAUGUUUGUGAGAUUUAUGGGAAACUUUGAGAAGACGUGUCUUAUCCCCAAUCAGAACGUCAAGCUCGUGGUUCUGCUUUUCAAUUCUGACUCCAACCCUGACAAGGCCAAACAAGUUGAACUGAUGAGAGAUUACCGCAUUAAGUACCCUAAAGCCGACAUGCAGAUUUUGCCUGUGUCUGGAGAGUUUUCAAGAGCCCUGGCCCUGGAAGUAGGAUCCUCCCAGUUUAACAAUGAAUCUUUGCUCUUCUUCUGCGACGUCGACCUCGUGUUUACUACAGAAUUCCUUCAGCGAUGUCGAGCAAAUACAGUUCUGGGCCAACAAAUAUAUUUUCCAAUCAUCUUCAGCCAGUAUGACCCAAAGAUUGUUUAUAGUGGGAAAGUUCCCAGUGACAACCAUUUUGCCUUUACUCAGAAAACUGGCUUCUGGAGAAACUAUGGGUUUGGCAUCACGUGUAUUUAUAAGGGAGAUCUUGUCCGAGUGGGUGGCUUUGAUGUUUCCAUCCAAGGCUGGGGGCUGGAGGAUGUGGACCUUUUCAACAAGGUUGUCCAGGCAGGUUUGAAGACGUUUAGGAGCCAGGAAGUAGGAGUAGUCCACGUCCACCAUCCUGUCUUUUGUGAUCCCAAUCUUGACCCCAAACAGUACAAAAUGUGCUUGGGGUCCAAAGCAUCGACCUAUGGGUCCACCCAGCAGCUGGCUGAGAUGUGGCUGGAAAAAAAUGAUCCAAGUUACAGUAAAAGCAGCAAUAAUAAUGGCUCAGUGAGGACAGCCUAAUGUCCAGCUUUGCUGGAAAAGACGUUUUUAAUUAUCUAAUUUAUUUUUCAAAAAUUUUUUGUAUGAUCAGUUUUUGAAGUCCGUAUACAAGGAUAUAUUUUACAAGUGGUUUUCUUACAUAGGACUCCUUUAAGAUUGAGCUUUCUGAACAAGAAGGUGAUCAGUGUUUGCCUUUGAACACAUCUUCUUGCUGAACAUUAUGUAGCAGACCUGCUUAACUUUGACUUGAAAUGUACCUGAUGAACAAAACUUUUUUAAAAAAAUGUUUUCUUUUGAGACCCUUUGCUCCAGUCCUAUGGCAGAAAACGUGAACAUUCCUGCAAAGUAUUAUUGUAACAAAACACUGUAACUCUGGUAAAUGUUCUGUUGUGAUUGUUAACAUUCCACAGAUUCUACCUUUUGUGUUUUGUUUUUUUUUUUUACAAUUGUUUUAAAGCCAUUUCAUGUUCCAGUUGUAAGAUAAGGAAAUGUGAUAAUAGCUGUUUCAUCAUUGUCUUCAGGAGAGCUUUCCAGAGUUGAUCAUUUCCUCUCAUGGUACUCUGCUCAGCAUGGCCACGUAGGUUUUUUGUUUGUUUUGUUUUGUUCUUUUUUUGAGACGGAGUCUCACUCUGUUACCCAGGCUGGAAUGCAGUGGCGCAAUCUUGGCUCACUUUAACCUCCACUUCCCUGGUUCAAGCAAUUCCCCUGCCUUUGCCUCCCGAGUAGCUGGGAUUACAGGCACACACCACCACGCCCAGCUAGUUUUUUUGUAUUUUUAGUAGAGACGGGGUUUCACCAUGCAAGCCCAGCUGGCCACGUAGGUUUUAAAGCAAGGGGCGUGAAGAAGGCACAGUGAGGUAUGUGGCUGUUCUCGUGGUAGUUCAUUCGGCCUAAAUAGACCUGGCAUUAAAUUUCAAGAAGGAUUUGGCAUUUUCUCUUCUUGACCCUUCUCUUUAAAGGGUAAAAUAUUAAUGUUUAGAAUGACAAAGAUGAAUUAUUACAAUAAAUCUGAUGUACACAGACUGAAACAUACACACAUACACCCUAAUCAAAACGUUGGGGAAAAAUGUAUUUGGUUUUGUUCCUUUCAUCCUGUCUGUGUUAUGUGGGUGGAGAUGGUUUUCAUUCUUUCAUUACUGUUUUGUUUUAUCCUUUGUAUCUGAAAUACCUUUAAUUUAUUUAAUAUCUGUUGUUCAGAGCUCUGCCAUUUCUUGAGUACCUGUUAGUUAGUAUUAUUUAUGUGUAUCGGGAGUGUGUUUAGUCUGUUUUAUUUGCAGUAAACCGAUCUCCAAAGAUUUCCUUUUGGAAACGCUUUUUCCCCUCCUUAAUUUUUAUAUUCCUUACUGUUUUACUAAAUAUUAAGUGUUCUUUGACAAUUUUGGUGCUCAUGUGUUUUGGGGACAAAAGUGAAAUGAAUCUGUCAUUAUACCAGAAAGUUAAAUUCUCAGAUCAAAUGUGCCUUAAUAAAUUUGUUUUCAUUUAGAUUUCAAACAGUGAUAGACUUGCCAUUUUAAUACACGUCAUUGGAGGGCUGCGUAUUUGUAAAUAGCCUGAUGCUCAUUUGGAAAAAUAAACCAGUGAACAAUAUUUUUCUAUUGUACUUUUCGAACCAUUUUGUCUCAUUAUUCCUGUUUUAGCUGAAGAAUUGUAUUACAUUUGGAGAGUAAAAAACUUAAACACGA